ACAUUGUUGGUGGGAAUAUAAAUUAGUACAAUCACUAUGGAGAACAGUUUGGAGGUUCCUCAGAAAACUAGAAAUAUAGUUACCGUAUGAUCUGGCAGUCUCACUGCUGGGUAUAUACCCAAAAUAAAGGAAAUCAGUGUAUGAAAGAUAUAUCUGCACUCCUAUAAUUGUCACAGCAUUACAUACAAUAGUUAGGAGCAACCUAAGUGUCCAUCAACAGAUGAUUGGAUAAAGAAAAUGUGGAGUCCUAUUCAGCCAUAAAAAAAGAAUGAGAUCGGCCGGGCGCGGUGGCUCACGCCUGUAAUCCCAGCACUUUGGGAGGCCGAGGCGGGCGGAUCACGAGGUCAGGAGAUCGAGACCAUCCCGGCUAAAACGGUGAAACCCCGUCUCUACUAAAAAUACAAAAAAUUAGCCGGGCGUAGUGGCGGGCGCCUGUAGUCCCAGCUACUUGGGAGGCUGAGGCAGGAGAAUGGCGUGAACCCGGGAGGCGGAGCUUGCAGUGAGCCGAGAUCCCGCCACUGCACUCCAGCCUGGGUGACAGAGCGAGACUCCGUCUCAAAAAAAAAAAAAAAAAAAAAAAAAAAAAAAGAAAAAAAGAAUGAGAUCUUAUCAUUUGCAAUAACAUGGGCAGAAUUGGAGAUUAUUAUGUUAAGUGAAAUAAUCCAGGUACAGAAAGACAAAUAUCACAUGUUCUCACUUCUUUGUGUGACCUAAAAAUCAUAAUAAUUGUACUCAUGAUAUAGAGAGUAGAAGGUUGGUUACCAGAGAUUGGGAAGGGUAGAGGGGGGUUAGGAGGAGGGUAGAUAGAUAAUGCGAUAAUAAUAGAUAAGUAAUAAUAAAUAAAUUAAUAAUAAAUAGAAUGAAUAAGACUGACUAUUUGAUAGCACAACAGGGUGACUAUAGUCAAUAAUAACUUAAUGGUAUGUUUUAAAAUAAUGUGAAGAAUAUAAUUCGAUUGUUUGUAACUCAAAGGAUAAAUGCUUGAGGAGAUGGACAUGCUAUUCUCCAUGAUGUACUUAUUUCCAAUUGCGUGCUUGUGUUAAGUACAUAUCAGGUACUGCAUAAAUUUAUACAUCUACUAUGUACUCACAGUAAUUUAAGAAAUAAAUAAAAAUAAAAAAUUAUAUAAUGUAUGAAAAAAGACAGUCACUAAAGUAUUCAUAGAGCCAUAGAUUAUAUAAUUUCAUUUAUGUGACCUUCAAUAAUUAGAUAAAACUAAACUGUAUUUUUUGGAAAUAAAUCCUGGAUGGUAAAAUUCUAAAAGAAAAGCAAGGAAAGUAUCUUUGUGGAGGAAGAAGUAGUGAUUAAGAGAGCACAGAGGAUGGGCUUCCCUGGUACUGACAAUGUUGUACUUCUUGACUUGAGUAGUAGUUGCAUGGGUGUUCACUUGUCAUUAAUCAUUCAGCCGAACAUGUUUAUUUUGUGCACUUUUCUGUAUAGAUAUUAUAUUUUACAAUUAUGGAGUUUUUAAAAGGAGACUUUUUAUUGGCAAGGAAACAUAUUCCUGAAGUAUCAUGAAGUGAAAACAGUUUACAAAAAAGAUGCAAACUAGAACCUCAGCGAACAUUAAAACUACAAAGACAUUACAUACAAAGUGCAAGAACUAAACUAGGAUGCUAUUAUUAACUAAAUUUUAUGCUAUUAUUAUCACUAUUAAUAAAAAUCUUUUAAAAUUUUUAUUAGAGAAGAAAGACAUGAAAGAGAAAUGAGUAAUAUAUAGAAAGAGAAAGGAUAAGAGAUAAUUAUUUGCAUAUGAUACAGUUUAAGUAUUUGGCCCCACCCAAAUCUCAUGUUGAAACAUAAUCCCCAGUGUUAUAGGUGGGGCCUGGUGAGGGGUGAUUGGAUCAUGGGGGCCAAUGUCUCAUGAAUGGUUUAAAGUCCUCCCCUUGGUGGUGUCCUCCAGGUAGUAAGUUCUCUUGAGAUCUGUUUGCUUAAAAGUGUGUGGCACCUCCACAGUCUCUCUCUUGCUUCUGCUCUGGCAAGGUGAUGUGUCUGCUUCCCCUUUGCCUUCUGCCAUAAUGUAAGUUUCCUGAGGGCCCCUCCAGAAGCUGAGCAGAUACUAGCAUCGUGAUUCCUGUACAGCCUGCAUAACCGUGAGCCAAUUCCACCUCUUUGCUUUAUACAUUACCCAGCCAUGGAUAUUUCUUUAUAGCAAUGCAAGAAUGGCCUAACACAAUAUAAUAUAAUUUUUCCUGGGAAAGAAUUUCCAGUGUUUUUUUCUAUGAAUUCCAAGGGCAUAUGCUUACACGGCCAGAAAAGAACAAUAAAAUCAGCAAAAUGCAAAAUUUACAACCAUUUCUACAUUUCUGAAAGUCCUGACAGUAAAAAAAAAAGUUCUAUUCCAAAAAGCAACAAAAAAGCUAACAAUUUCAAAAUAACUGUUAGCAAGAUAAGUGUAGGUUCUUUAAAUAAAAAUUUAAAAAACUCUUAUUUUAUAUAUUAAUUUCAACCAAAUUUCAGUCAAUAUUUGUUUAGAAGUUUGGCAAAACAAAAAUAAAACAAAACACAAAUAUUAAAGAAAGAACUAAGGGAAAAGAUAUUGAGGAGAGAACCAGUUCUACGAGAUAUUACACCAUUUACAAAGCACCAAUAAUUAAAAUAUUAGGUAAUUGGCACAAGAAUAGUGAAAACGUUAGAAUUUUAUAAACUAUCACAAUUAGCUUUUAUUAUAGAUAAAAUGGACAAGUUAGAAUCACAAAAUUGGGUAGAUAUACUAGACAUGCAAUCUCAAUUCAUGCUUUUACCAAAAUAAAUUCAGAUUUAUUAAGGGGUUAAGUAUACUUUUAAUCAAUAACAAAUAAAAUCUUAAAUAAAAAUAAAACAGCAUGUUUGCCUGUCAAAUUAGCAAAUAAAAACAAUAGAGUACACUGGUGGUAGUUAGGAUAAAUGAAAUAGGUACAUGUUUCUAUGUGAAUGUAAAUUCAUACAAUUAUUUUGAAAGACUGUUUUGCAAUAUAGAUAAAAAUCCUUAAAAUUCUAUGUCAAUAUUGAUCAGAGACUUCUGAUAACCUAACAAAAAAUUCUAAUUCAUAAAUAAGCUUUUAUAUGAAAGACAGCAUUAUUUACAUACCAUAAAAUUAUUUGUAGUAUAAUCUAAACAUUUUAUACCUUAUGUUCUCAUAUAAGUCAAACCUCAGAAAAAAAACAUAAAAAUAACUAAAUUUUAACAGAGAGUACAUCUGUGAUAGAAUAACUGGCUACUUAAAAAAAUUAACAUUGUAUGCAUGUAUUUUUUUAAUGAUAAAAAUAUGCCCUUUUUAAAAGCAGAAAAAUGUUCACUAAAACCAUUGUAAAAGUAAAAUACAUAUCAGUAAGCUUCUUUAGAGUUCCUUCCCCUAUACUUUGUCAUGACUCUUUAACCUAAAUUUAUCACUUAAUUACUCAUUGAAAAUAUAAUUUUGCAAAAAUCAAUCUAUAAUCAAUUUGUAGACAGAGGGUUGAAGACAAAGACACUUGAAUAUUUGGAUGUUUUCAAUUGGAAUCAGUGUGUCCAACUGUAUGAUAAAAUUAAACUAAUUUGACCAUUUUAUUUAUUUAAAUCUAUGAUUCCAUGCUUGUCACAUGUCUAGGGGUUAAAAGUGUCAGUUGUGAAAAUGUGAUUCAUUAACAUAUGUUUGAGAGAGUGUUGAUGGUGUUUGGACUUACCAAUGAUGUGGCAAGGAAUAAUUUUAACAUGUAUCAAGGAAUGUAGUUUUAGCUGAUAUAAUUCUAUGGGGAAUUUAUCAACCAUUUCCAAAAUAUUUGUGUGAUUGAUUAUCUGAGAUAUAGAUGGAGCUUGUGAGAAGUACAUGAGCCCUGUCUCUAUGGGCAAUGGAAGAACGUGGGUAGGAGGCCUAAUACCCUCCUAACCAAAAGAUACGAAGGUGAUUAACAUGAAGUAGGCUUUAGGAUAUUGUAAGCUUCAUUAGGGGCUGGGCUUCUAGUAAUCUUUCAUCAAAUACAGGGCUUCAGGUAAAUGUCUUUGAAAACAUAGCUUUAAUGUGAAGCCAAAUGGGAUCACCUUUUCUCAGUCCAGUUUUAGGCCUCAAGAUCUUCUUGUAAAGAUAAGCUGAGUUUUUUUUCAGUAAACCUUGAAUAGUCAGCCCUUUAUCUAGCCAGCUGCAAAAUCCAAGGACUUGCUGCCACAUGCCAUUUCCAGUCAGGUCAGAAAGAAAGAAUACUGGAGGUUAUGGAUGGUGAGUGGGUGAUUUGGUGUACUUAGAUCUGUAACUACAAUUGCUGGAAUGGGCCAAUGAUCAUGAGCACUAAUUUGAAUGCAGGCAAGUCUAAGAGAAAAAUACAUUUUUGCACAUAUAUGCAUGGGCUUUAUGUUGUGAUUUAUGUAUGGCCCCAGGAUUAGCUUCCUUACAGAAGAACAAGAGACUGUAAAUGUUCUCUCAAAUGAUCCUCUAUUUUGGAAAAGGUGUGGCUAUCUGAGAAGAGAAUGAUGCAAUUUGUCUCUAAAACAGUGCCCCUAAAACUAUAAUAUAUACACGACUUACGUGGGAAUCUCGUUUAAAUGCAGAUCCUGAUUGAGGUGGUCUGAUGCAGGGCAUGAUCUACCGCCCAGGUGUUGCUGAUGCUGCUAGUUUGUGGACCACUCUUUGUGUAGCAUAAGUCUAAGAGAAAUAGCUAAACCCUUUUGUCCCAUCUUUAUCAUAUCUUUUGAUAUUAUAUAGCAAAACAGAUACAUCCAAUAACCUAUGUCUGUCUUUUUGACCAUAUACUUAAACUCAUUGACCCUCUAUUUAUAAAUUUCUAAAACAGGUGAUAACUCUUGCCUUGUGUUAUAGAACAGGUUAGAAAUAAUGUAUGUAAAGUACCUAUUAUAGAACAGAUUCUGGCUCAUUGUAAAUCUCUUCUCCACCCGGUAGUGACUAUUAAUGUAAUUAUUACAUAAAAGAAAGGGGGGUGGGGUUUAACUAAAAUAAGUUGCAACUAAUCAUUUGAAUUCAGACUCUAAAAUAACUCAAAAAGACAAUCGCGUGAUUAAAGAUGUACAUGAAAGAAUAUGAGAACCAAAAAAGUAAACAUUAUCUAGGUUCUAUUAAUAGAGGUUAAAUAUCUAUAUUAAGGGAGAUACUGCAGAGACAUCUGGAAUUUUCAAGGAGAUAUUAUGAACUCAAAAGUUAUUUAUCUAUUGAAACUUGUUACUGAAUAAUAACAAGUUGGACUUGGAAAUACUGUGGUCAACUCCAAGGUUAUUAUUUUUAUUCUGGUAUGCUGAUGGAUAAAGUAUACUCAAGGAGGGCGGCACUGAUGGUAAUUUUUCCAAAGGCAUUAUCUGAGAUAUAGAUGGAGCUUCUGAGAAAUACAUGCUUGGGAAAUGUUUGAAAGAGGUUAGCACAUAUUCUCCCAGAAACAAGAAGAUUGGACAGAAAUUGAGCGCUUAGGCUGAGGAACCAUGUGAAAGGAAUAAAUAAAUAGUCUUACCUUUAUCAUACUCCUGGGGCAAAACUGAUACUUGCCAAAAUUAUAUGUUGACAGUUGUAUUCUUAAUAUAAGAAGCUAUUUCUAAUUUCUCAAGUUUUCCCCCCCAAAUAGCCACUAUAUUCAUAAGGUAACUGUUGUUUUAAUAGAAUGUAAAAGCAAAUGCCUUUAUGCCAUCCCUGCAGGAAUUUAGACCAGACUUAUGGUAAAACUGAAGAGUUGAGCUAAGAUCUUCAUUUCUAAGUUCCAGUAUUUGAAUACAUUAGAUAUUAGCCAAGAAAUACUACUUAAUUGUUUUUAUAGGCACCAACAGAAAUGAUUUUAUAGUAAUAAGAAGACGCAAUAAUCUGUAGUGUUUUAAAGUGUUCAAAAUGCUUGUAUGCACAUUACCUCACUUAACAUUUUAGAAAUUUAUUAAUUUGCUAGUGUUUUAGCUUACUCUGCCCUUAUAAGGAAGGCUUGGAAUGGAGAAGGGCCUGGAAAUGGGUGAUAGGUUAGUGAACCAAUGGUGUUUGUCAAUCCCACCUUUUACUCACUAGUCUUUACUGAGUCAUUCUAAAGGUUUUGACUUAAUAGAUACAACUCCUUUUCUUUGUAUCUAUCUUUUAGUAGUAGUAUUUGUAAAAAUUAAGUUACAUAAUUACAAUAUUAAAUUUAACUGGCAUAUGAAUGUUUUGAGAAUAAAUACAAUUGAUUUUGACAAGCAUGCAAUUCACUGGUAAAAACAAAAAUCAUGGGUAUUAUUCCAAAAUCACUACUAGCUGGAAGGAUGCAGUGUUCCCUGGAUAUUGUUGAAUAUAUUUGCACGGGAAGUUUUCAGGUAAUGAGAUUAAGUAGUGACUGAUUAAGAAAAUUAAAACUUUUUCACAGUCAUUUUUAUCAUCAUCAUCAUCACCUAUAAAUGUACUUUUUUAUAAAUAUGUUUUGGUGUGUGUCCUAAAAUCCUUUCUGGCUCUGGAAAGGAUAUUCUUCGCAGGGCCAGAAAGGAAUAUCUAUAUCUAUAUCUAUAUCUAUAUCUAUUUCUAUAUCUAUAUCUAUAUCUAUAUCUGUAUCUAUUUGAGUUUCUAGAUAUAUAUCUAUAUCUCUGAGCUUAUAGAUAUACAGAGAUAUAUAGUUAUAUAGAUAUGGAUAUAUGUAGUUAAACAUCUCUAAUUUAAACCAGUCUCCUAGAGUAAUGCAACAUAUACAAUCCACCUUAUUUGGGAUCAGUAAGGGGCCAAUCUGUGUCUUACUCAUCUUAGUGUUGCCAAGAGCCAAAAUCUGGACUCAGUAAAGGUUUGUGUUGAAUAAUUAUGAUAAUGUUAAAGUGUUAGAAUGUUACAUUGUGUGAUAUGUUACCAACUUAUUAAGAAUCUGAGUUCUGAUGAAUUAGAUGUUUAUACGUUCUGUAUAUCUGCCAAUGAAGUAGUUAAAUCACCUUUAUUUAUCAGAUGGAAAGUGCCUUGAAAGUUUGGCAUUCUACGAUUUGGCAUAGUCUAUGAAGCAAGUAAACACCAAAAUCAACACAUUUCCUGUGUAAUCAAAAGUUCCUAUACAUUACUAGCAAUUCUAAAUUGUUUUGCUAAUUGCACAGAAAGUCUACUAAUGCCCAAAACAUCAAGAACAUACUAACAAUCAAAUAAUAGUAAAAGUAAUAGAUUGUAAAUACUUAAGUGGGAGAAAAUUUUGCAUGCUUUCCCUGCUAGAGACCAGAAAACAUAAGUUUCAUAUCCUUUUACAAAUGAAAGAGCAUCCUACUUCUGUUUAUGUUAACAGCUGGAGCUACCAUUAAUUUUAUUUUGUUGUUCUCAUACUCUUUAUAGCUUGAGGCAAUAAUUCACUCAACUUGUGAAAUAGUUACAUCACCAAUUUUGAUGCUCGGUAUGUUUUCAUGUGUAUUUGGUGAAUUUCUUUUAAAUUAUUAAGCAUUUUUUUUCUGCAUUAUGUGGGAUAGAGGUAGUUUCAGUAUUAAAUAAUCUAAAUUCAGUGUAAGUCAUAAACAUAGCAUUAAAACUUUUUUGAUCUUUCUUAUGGGAUUGCUGUAUUGUUAUUUUUAAAGCUGUCACAUAAUUAGUAAUUCUAUAGCAGUUUUCUUAUUCUAGAAUGACAGAGUUUAGAAGUAGUCCACUGGUAAAAUUUUUAUAUAUUUAAAAAUAUAAAUCGUAAUGAUCAGUAUUUCAAAUUUGCUACAUUGUAUUUAAUUCUGGCUUUACCAUAAAGCUAUCUAAUUUUUUCACAUUCUAAUGAUUUAUUAAUAUAUAGCUGACAAGAUCGAAACCUAUUCAAUGAUUAUGCGUGUGUUGUAUCAUUUAACUUAGUAUUUAAAUGCUCAUUGUUCUGAGCUGCAGCACAAGCAAUCAAUCAUAUAUUGCUUAAUUUGGAAUAGAAUUUGUUGAGGGAUGUCACUUUUCUGGCUAUCCCCGCCUCUAAAAUAGUUACAAUUAAGAAUUUUAUAAAGUUGAUCAUAAGUUUCACAAUUCAUGUAUUUUCAGUAGCAUAUUCGUAAAGUUAAAUUGGCAUCAGUUUGGUAAAAUGGCAGCAUGCAUUAAACUGUAUUUGUGGAUAAGUCUUUUUCAUAAGACACAGGAAACUAUAAGCAUUAGGGCAAGUAAAACUUUAAAAAUAAAAACAUGUAACUCAAAUAUGUAAUUCUGUAAUUCUUGCUUCAUUCUUUUAUUUCUUCCAUUUAACAAAGCAAAACAUUUUAUCUCAGUCUGCCACAUUCUAAUCUUUUAUUUUACUGACACUGUUUUGUGGGAGAGUAUAAGAAGUUGAUUAAUAUACCUGAGACAGACAGGAUAAAUCUCUAUUGUGGUAUCUGAUGUAGAAGGGGCAACCGACUUCUGAGAGAGGCCAUCUAAGGAAAUGUGUUUUCUGGAUCUGAGACAUCAAAAUUAUCUGGGGUUUUAUUAUAAAGUAAGAAAUCUAUGCCCAUCACUCAAGAUUUGAUUUAGUACAACUGAGUUGCACCUGGAUAUUAAUCUUUGUUUACACACAGGUAAUGUUAAGCAUGCUAAAGUUUUGAAAAACACUGAUACAUUAAUUCUUCAUUUUUUUCUCGAUUCUUUAUCAUAUUGAAUACCUAGAAAUCAGCAUUAACCUCAUUCACAGUUUAAUACUACAAUAUAACCAUGAAGUGCAUUUCUGUAUAUUGUACAAAACAAACUGUUCAGGACAUUGUACAUUAUAUUUCUCAAUGAUCUUUACAUGCCAAUUCAUAUCAAACAUUCUUUUAGAACUAUAAAAGAAACAAGAAGGUUUCUUGAAAUAAUGAAUCUUUUUAAUGUAAGAAGAAACAUGCAAUCAGCAUCUUCAUCUCUUUUUGCUUCGACAGUAUGGAACUGUGGUAGGCAACCUCUAAUAUCCCUGCUUCUUGGUUACAUACCCUUUGGAAUACCCCUGCCUUGAGUAUCAGUUGGAUUACUACUUGCCUCUGACUAAUAGAAUACAGAAUGAUUGAUUGAAUGUCACUUCUGAGAUUAAGUUUUGAAAAGACUGUGACUUUCAUCAUGGGUGAUCUCUCUCACUUGUUCCAAGGGAAGUCAAGUGUAUGUUGUAAAGUACCCUCUGGAUAGGCCUACAUGGCAAGGAUUUGAAGAAAGCCUCUGGUUAGCAGCUAGUGAGGAACUGAGAUGCUGUUUCCAAUAGCCUGCAAAGAACUGAAUCUUGCCAACAAGCAUGUGAGUGGGCUUAGAAGCAGAAUCAAACUCAGUCAUGCUUCAUAUAAGACCACAGCUUCCAACAAUUCCCCAACUGCAACUUCAUGAGAAACCUUGAUCCAGAAGCUCCCAGCUAUACCAACCCCCAAUUUCUAACCAACAGAAAAUGUGAAAUAACUUGUUUGAUGUUUUAAGUUGUAAAGUUUUAGAAUAAUUUGUUAUGUAGCAAUAGAUAACAAUACAGAAACCAAGAGCUUCAUUAAUCACCUCACCUCAGAUUCUCAUAUCAAAAUUUUUCUUAUGUGAUCACUAAUCUUUCUUCUUAUAUAAUUUUAUUUAUCACAGGUGAGUUUUAUAUUAAAUUACUUCAAAUCCUUUUUAAAAAUCAGAUGGUUAUUAAUAGUAAAAAAUUUCACAGAUAACUCAUAACUCUUUGUGCCUAGUAAAUCAGGCCUCCCCUAGACCAUCUUUGUCAUUUAAUCCAAAUUGAAACUGCAAACUCAUUUAUAUUUGAUCUGAUAAUUAAUCAAACUCUUUCUCAGCAGAAUUACCUUUCUAGUACUUAGAUCAAAAUCAUUGCAUCACAGAAUACUAGCACUGGAAUGUAUCUUAAAUAUUCUGGAGAUCAGCCCUUUUGUUUUAUGGAUGAGUAAUCUUAGAUCUAAAAAAAGAAGAAGAAAAAAAAGAUACAGCAAAUUACCCAAGAUGGAGCUGUUGCUUGAACUGAGAUCUGAUGACUCUUUUCCAGUGCUCAUUUGAUUCCUUGAUCAUAAAUUUACUGGGUGGUUGAAGAUGCUAAGAAGUGUUUUGAGAGAUGGGUGAUAUGUAGCCCAGGUCUUGAACAUUUUCAUGUAUAAAUUCCAAAAUGGGAUAGUUCAUUUGUACUAAUAUUUCAAAACUGCUAUCAAAUUUCUCAUGGCUCUGUAUACUAUAGAGGAAUGUUACAAAAAACAUUGAGAUUAGAGAAAAACCACGUCCCUAAAAGGUAAACUUAUCUGUGACUAUUUCUUACUACUAAAUAACAUUUUAUCGAGUCCCUAGUGUCUUCCUUUUCUAUGAUGACAUCACAAAGUUGUUGUACUACCAAUGUUCAAAAGCAAAACAUUGGUGGUGUUCAUUAGUAACAUAAUUCAGAUUGUAUUGUGGAUCUAUUGUGUAUAGAUGGGAGUUUGGCUCAUUUCUAAGUGAACAAACAAAAUGAAGAUUAAGACAGAGGCACUAAAGUUCCCUGCCUAAAGAGCCAGGUCUUUAAUAGUUGACUAGGUGCAAGACUCAGAAUUAACUAUUUCAUGUCAGUGUUAUUAUGAAUGAAGAUUUAACAACAUAAUGUGUACUUUAGAAAGUAUCAGUUGCUUUCCAGCAUUAAGUAACAUAUUUCUUAUUUAUAUCAAUUAUCUCUUUUCGAAAGAGAGAAGUUGGUUUUUUUUUUUUUUUUUUUUUUUGGCCUGAGAUAAAAUAAUUUCCUUUAUCUCCCACUUGAUUUUACAAGUGCUGACUAGCUCUUGCUAGUUUUAUGUAAUUGCAUGGAAAGUUCUGGAAUACCUCUCUGGUUGCACUUGGUGGUGAAGUUAUUACACAAAUAAAUGCCAGGAAGUCAGUUAUUUGCUUUCCUAUUACUAUGCACUGUUGGAGGCAUUACUAUCGUCUCUUGUUUAAAUAAAUUUCACCAUGUCUUCACACCCCCAGGCCUAAAUUAAAUCAAAGUAGUUUUAGAGCUCAAGGACAGAAUAAGUCACUAUGGGAAAGUGGGACAAAGGAAAUCAAGCACGCCAGAUGGAAAGUUCAGACUGGCCAGUAUCUUUAAAAUGUCAGUGCUGUAUAAAAAGGCUUUAUAAGCCAUCAGUCAACGAUGGCUCUAGAAACAGGCCAGUGGCUACAGAAAUUAGGCUUUUUUCACUAAGCCUUGAAAAUUUAUUUUCAAAGUGGGUUGAAUUUUAGGUCAUUUGUGCGGGUAUAUCUAAUGAAGAGAAAAACAAAGUGAUGGAGAAGGAAUUUCUAAUAAGAUCUUAGUAUUCAUUAGAAAUAUAACCUCUUGCUUUCAUAAUUAAUAGGAUCUGAAGUUAAUUUAAUAAAAAUUUGACUUAUAUACUAAAACAGGCAAGAUUUGAACCUGGCUUUAUUAAGUUUUUAUUUUAGUUUACAUGUUUGUUUCAAACAAGAUUAAAAAUUAAGAAUUAAAAAUUGAUGUUUGUCUGGAUUUUUACAACCAAUUAUUAGAUCUAUGGCAGGUAUCCAGCCAUUUAAAAAUAACAGUGUAAAGCAAAGCCUCUAAUUUUAAAGAAGAAAAGGAAUCCGAAAGAGGGAUGGCUAUAGCAACCUUGAUGAUAAAGGAAAAUUUGUGCAGAAAAGCCUGCAGUAAACAGAUUUUCUUAGACUUAAGGCAUGUCCUUAGUUUAUCAUACUCAGAAAAAAAAAAAAAGAUCUCCUUAGUUGUGUAGCUAUUUCAUCUUAACUGAAUUCACAGUAGCUAAAAUAUGCAUGUAACAGUAUUAGCUAAAUUUAUAGGCUAGGCACGGUGGCUCACACCUGUAAUCCCAGGAGUUUGGGAGACCCAGGCAGGCGGAUCACCUCACCUGAGGUCAGGAGUUCAAGACCAGCCUGGCCAACAUGGUGAUAUACCGUCUCUACUAAAAAUACAAAAAUUAUCCUGGCAUGGUGACGGGUGCCUGUAAUCCCAGCUACUUGGAAGGCUGAGACAGGAGAAUUGCUUGAAUCCCGGGAGACAGAGGUCGCCAUGAGCCAAGACAGUGCCAUUGCACUCCAGCCUGGGCAACAAGAGCAAAAUUCCAUCUCAAAAAACAAUUAUAGAGCACUCUAUACACACCAGACACUUGUGCAAACUCAUGAUCAUAUAUUUAACUGUUAAAAUAGUCCUUUGAGGUAGAUACUAGUAAUGAGGAAAUCAUGAUAAACAAUCUGUAUUAACAAAUCCCUGCUUUAUAUCAUUAUCCCUACUCCAAGAUUUCUAAUAUUGUUGAAACAUUCAAAAUAUGGAUUGUGUGGUGGGUUAGUGCACAGACUGUGGGGUUACCUACUUGGUUUCAAAUACUGGCUCUGUCACGUUCUAGCUAUGGCACUUUAGAUAAUUUGAUCUCUUCCUACUUUUGAGUUUCUUCAUGUAUAAAACGAACUCUAAAAGGACUAUUCUGAGGAUUAAAUGAGAUAGAAGCUGUAAAACUAUCUGUAACAGAACCUAGCACAUAGUAUGAAUGUCAUAAUUGUCAGCUGUUUUUAUUAUUUCGAUUUCCUUUAGGAUUCCCAGGCAAGAAAUGCACAAUUGUAACAUUUGUAACAUUUGGUUAAUAUAUUUAACUACACAAGUUAAGUAUUAGAAGAUAUUUUUUAAAAUAUACAUUUUCUGCCUUCAAGUGUCAUAUAAUUCAAAUAGAGAUUAUAAAGAAUCACAUAUGCAAUGUAUUGUAUUUGCAAUGCUUUCUGCAAUACUGUAGCACAAAUAAAAUAUAAUUUUAUCUAAAUUGUGUUCAUCAGAGAUUUUAAUCAGAAUGUAGUUGAUUUUUUAGAGAUUGGCUUUAAGAAUAACUUUAUUUUAAUAGUUUAUAUACAUAUAUAUAUAUCACAUAGAGAUCGUCAGAAGGUUAGAAACAAAAAAGUGUGAAGAGUAAAGUAAACAUUACCCAUAAAUUAACAAUCCAGAUUUUUCAAAAAUUACUAAUAUUUUGGCAUGCUAACUUAAAGUCUUUGUGUGUGUGUAUAACUAUAUAUUUUAAAAUAACUGCAUCACUUUUUACAUAGAAAUUUGUUAUCCUUUUUUCCACUCAACAUUAUUUAAUAAAAAAUUUUCCAGUUUAUUAAAUGUGGGUCUGAUGAGUUAGCUAAGGAAAAGAGAAUAGUACUCCUUGACUUUGGGGGUGGGAACUGAGGAAUAAGCAGUAAACAUAAGAAAAUAGUGAGUUUUAUUUAGUGAAUGGUGAGGUAAUUUAUUUGGUUUUAAAAUAGCAGGAAAGGUAGGAGUUAAUUUUACAUAUGCAGGUAGGAGUUAAUAUCCAGUCCUGCAGUCCAGGCAGGAUGACGCUCUGUGGAAUAGUGGGACGAGCAGUGGGGAGUGAGGGGCCUCAGUACACACCAUAUUAGUCAUAUUCAACACUUCAACAAUAUCAAGUUUGUUAAUUGAUGGCCACUUCACCUGUGACAUGUGACUUGACCCUCCUCUUCCCUUGUUUCUUCAUCUUUAAAAUGUGACAUCUGAAAUAUGGGCCCCAAAUUAAUAAUGUACCAUUUUAGGCCAAAGCUAUCCCAUGACUAUUGCCUAGAACGGGAGAGGUGAACAGAAGAGGUAGGGGCUGUGAAUGCUUUCGCAAAACUGACAAGCAGGGCGAAAGGGAAACUCUGGAAUAUGAGCUUCCAGGCUGCACUUGCAUCUUGUUUAUCUCACGGUUCUCAGGGGCCACCACCUUACCUGGCACACCGAAUGUGCCUGAGGAAUGCUUGAUGCACUAAACCACAAAUCAGUGCAAUGGAAUUGCCAUCCCCCAAAAGUCCUUUUUUAAGAUAAGAACGUAUUUUCUGAAGUGGAUUCUGAUAGCUAUUAGUUUUGGUGGUCUGGAGUAUGCUUUUACUCUUUCUCCCUGAUACUGGCAAUAGAACACAUAGGUCCACAGGUUUGGAUAUGAGACUAGGUUCUUGCUAAUUGUAUAGUCCGCUUCAUUUUGACAUAGUGACUGAUUCAUAAGGGUAGGACAGUCAAUCAAAUAUAUUUGUAGAAUUAAAUGUGGAAGAAAAAAUAUUUGUGCAUUUGGUUAAAAUAUCAAGGACUGGAUUUACCCUCUUUCCAGAAACAAGUAAAAACUGUAUACAGCAUUUGAAGCAAUGGCACUCGACAUUGGCAUGAGGCAGUGGAUGGAAGUGAUUGCUAGAAGAUGGAUAAUGAAAGAGGUGACUGGUAAAAAGAUGGCCUAUCAGAAGGUCCAUGCAGAUCAAAGAGCUCCAGGACACUCACAGUACUUAGACAAUGAUGACCUUCAAGCCACUGCCCUUGACUUAGAGUGGGACAUGGAGAAGGAACUAGAGGAGUCUGGUUUUGACCAAUUCCAGCUAGACGGUGCUGAGAAUCAGAACCUAGGGCAUUCAGAGACUAUAGACCUCAAUCUUGAUUCCAUUCAACCAGCAACUUCACCCAAAGGAAGGUUCCAGAGACUUCAAGAAGAAUCUGACUACAUUACCCAUUAUACACGAUCUGCACCAAAGAGCAAUCGCUGCAACUUUUGCCACGUCUUAAAAAUACUUUGCACAGCCACCAUUUUAUUUAUUUUUGGGAUUUUGAUAGGUUAUUAUGUACAUACAAAUUGCCCUUCAGAUGCUCCAUCUUCAGGAACAGUUGAUCCUCAGUUAUAUCAAGAGAUUCUCAAGACAAUCCAGGCAGAAGAUAUUAAGAAGUCUUUCAGAAAUUUGGUACAACUAUAUAAAAAUGAAGAUGACAUGGAAAUUUCAAAGAAGAUUAAGACUCAGUGGACCUCUUUGGGCCUAGAAGAUGUACAGUUUGUAAAUUACUCUGUGCUGCUUGAUCUGCCAGGCCCUUCUCCCAGCACUGUGACUCUGAGCAGCAGUGGUCAAUGCUUUCAUCCUAAUGGCCAGCCUUGCAGUGAAGAAGCCAGAAAAGAUAGCAGCCAAGACCUGCUCUAUUCAUAUGCAGCCUAUUCUGCCAAAGGAACUCUCAAGGCUGAAGUCAUCGAUGUGAGUUAUGGAAUGGCAGAUGAUUUAAAAAGGAUUAGGAAAAUAAAAAACGUAACAAAUCAGAUCGCACUCCUGAAAUUAGGAAAAUUGCCACUGCUUUAUAAGCUUUCCUCAUUGGAAAAGGCUGGAUUUGGAGGUGUUCUUCUGUAUAUCGAUCCUUGUGAUUUGCCAAAGACUGUGAAUCCUAGCCAUGAUACCUUCAUGGUGUCACUGAAUCCAGGAGGAGACCCUUCUACGCCUGGUUACCCAAGUGUCGAUGAAAGUUUUAGACAAAGCCGAUCAAACCUCACCUCUCUAUUAGUGCAGCCCAUCUCUGCACCCCUCGUUGCAAAACUGAUCUCUUCGCCAAAAGCUAGAACCAAAAAUGAAGCGUGUAGCUCUCUAGAGCUUCCAAAUAAUGAAAUAAGAGUCGUCAGCAUGCAAGUUCAGACAGUCACAAAAUUGAAAACAGUUACUAAUGUUGUUGGAUUUGUAAUGGGCUUGACAUCUCCAGACCGGUAUAUCAUAGUUGGCAGCCAUCAUCACACUGCACACAGUUAUAAUGGACAAGAAUGGGCCAGUAGUACUGCAAUAAUCACAGCGUUUAUCCGUGCCUUGAUGUCAAAAGUUAAGAGAGGGUGGAGACCAGACCGAACUAUUGUUUUCUGUUCUUGGGGAGGAACAGCUUUUGGCAAUAUUGGCUCAUAUGAAUGGGGAGAGGAUUUCAAGAAGGUUCUUCAGAAAAAUGUUGUGGCUUAUAUUAGCCUCCACAGUCCCAUAAGGGGGAACUCUAGUCUGUAUCCUGUAGCAUCACCAUCUCUUCAGCAACUGGUAGUAGAGAAAAAUAAUUUCAACUGUACCAGAAGAGCCCAGUGCCCAGAAACCAAUAUCAGUUCUAUACAGAUACAAGGUGAUGCUGAUUAUUUCAUCAACCAUCUUGGAGUUCCCAUCGUGCAGUUUGCUUACGAGGACAUCAAAACAUUAGAGGGUCCAAGUUUUCUCUCCGAGGCCCGUUUUUCUACACGAGCAACAAAAAUUGAAGAAAUGGAUCCCUCUUUCAACCUUCAUGAAACCAUUACUAAGCUCUCAGGAGAAGUGAUUUUGCAAAUUGCCAACGAACCUGUUCUGCCCUUUAAUGCACUUGAUAUAGCUUUAGAAGUUCAAAACAACCUUAAAGGUGAUCAACCCAACACUCAUCAACUGUUAGCCAUGGCGUUACGCCUGCGGGAGAGUGCUGAACUUUUUCAGUCUGAUGAGAUGCGACCUGCUAAUGAUCCCAAGGAGAGAGCACCCAUCCGCAUCCGGAUGCUGAAUGACAUUCUCCAAGACAUGGAGAAAAGCUUUCUGGUAAAGCAGGCACCACCAGGUUUUUAUAGAAACAUCCUCUACCACCUUGAUGAAAAGACAAGCCGGUUUUCAAUACUUAUAGAGGCUUGGGAACACUGCAAACCCCUUGCAUCAAAUGAGACCCUUCAAGAAGCCCUGUCAGAGGUGUUGAACAGCAUUAAUUCAGCUCAGGUUUACUUCAAAGCAGGACUUGAUGUGUUCAAGAGUGUCUUGGAUGGGAAGAAUUGAGAAAACUCUGAGCAUUUUUAAAAGUUUGUUUACAAUUCCACAAGCAAAAGCUCUAAUUUAACCAGAUUUUCUGACAUUGAAGGCUUAUUUUCCCCAAUGGCUUUUUGACAAGUAUAAAGCUAUUAUUACAUUGUAUUUUUUAAAUGUAAAUAUAGAAAGAACAUUUUGCACAUUUAAUAUUUUUCUUAUAUCUACAUUUCUGAAUAUGUAAAGCAAGUUAUUGAAAUAGGACUUAAGAAUUACCUAUUAAAAAGAAAUCUGAUAUAUAAAAAUAUGUACUAUUUUAAGGAAAAAUUUCCAAGAAGUUCUGGACUAUCUUUGUUCCUAUGGGGAGGGCAUAUAGGAACACAGUUUAUUCUCUCUGAUAGAGCUAUUAAUGACUUAGUUUCUGUAAAAGAAAUGGAGAGUUGAUAUGGUUCAGAUUAACUUCACUAUUAAGUGUUCAAUAUGAAGAAUUCAAGUAUUCUGACUGAGUGAUUGGUUGACCUAAACCACUUUGAAUGUUUCUAUUUUAUGAAAUGAAGUUUCUCUUCUUAACACAACUAGAUGUAGUAAUACACUGGUUAUGAAAUUGUAUUUUUUUAAGUAUUAAUGAAAAAAGAGCCAUAAGCAUUCCAGGAGAAAAUCUCAAGGGAGCUACAUAGAGCAAUUUAAAUGCAAAUUUUUUUCCUAACAACUUACAAGGUGACUAGCUUUGAAACCCCUAAUUUGCCUCAGUUGAUUUUCUAAGAAUUUCAGGAGUGAUGUAUGUCUUAAGAGGGAGAAAAAAAUAUUUCUUAUUACUUUUUCUCUUGUUUCUGUUGGAAACACUGAAGCAGGGACUCUAAAAUGAAAGCAUCUCACAUUGGUUUUCUUUCUUGUAUCUUUUCUGAAACUCCUUGCUGUAAGGCAGCUUUCUCAGAGUACUAUAUAUUUUCAACAGUAAAGUAGCAGAGUUUCUCUUUGAAACCCAAAAUGUCUUCUAAAGAAUCAAAUUUCUAUUUCUGCCUCUGACAAAAAGAACUUACUAUGAAAGAAAUAGUUGUUUUAUCAAUAAAAGCCCCUUAAUAUUAUGAAGAAACUUUUCAUAUUUUUUCUUCUUUAUCCUUAAUUGUGACUAAGAUGGAAAUCUAGAAAAUAUUCAUGCUUCUAAGUUUCUGCAGUGUUACUGUAAGAGAGUGUCUCGUCUACACUUCAGUUCUUCUCUCAUGUGGAAAACUAAGCUUUUUAUAUUGACAUUGCCAUUGAAUAGCUCUAGCAACUAUUAUUAUUCCCCCAAACCCUAAAAUUCUACCUAUUAGGUGUCAGGUUAAAGUUCUAAUUUAUCUUUAGAAAUUUAUGUGAAAAAUGGUUUUCCUAUACUGGAUAAAGCAAUUCCCCUUAGGAAACAUAGCCUCAGAGUAUUUCAUAUAAAUUUUCUCUAUCUAAUUCAAACAUAUCUCCCCAUGAUACACCGCCAGAGUGACAUUGCAGACAGUCUGUGUAUGUUUAAAUUUUCACUUUUUAUGGAUGAGCAUAAACCUAGUCUUAGUUUAAAGGCAAACUAAAGUUGAGGGGAAAUAAUUAAUCAAUACUGAUUAAUUGAUUUAUAAGGUUCAACACUGUCUACCCUAAAUAAUUUUUAUAUGCUCAAGGCAAAGCAGGGAAUAGAGGCAAUUAGCUAGAUAAUUCAAGCAGAAAUCCAUUUUCAUCGAAAUUGCCUGUGUGCACAUAUUUUUAGAUGAAAAAUGAAACUACCUUACAAUAUUAUUUUUUUAACCAAUGUAUUUGUUUGCAAACAUUUGCCAUGUUGAAGAGUGUGUAUAGGAAAGGUCUAGAAAUAAAUAGGCUUGUGCAUACCUAGGCAUUCAUGCUCUUUCUUCCUCUUCAGAGAUCAUCAGAAAAGAGGUGGGAAUACACAAGCAGGUGCAUGUAAGCCCAAAAGCUAGAAAGCCUUAUAUUUAACCAAAGGUUGAUGUGUUCAUUCCAGUUAUUCACUUACAGAUGAAACUAAAACAAAUAAAGGCAAGCUAUUAUCAGUUUGGUAGUUCAUUAUUUUAGAACAAAUUUCUAAAUUAAUUUAUUCCCAUAACCUACAAUAGCACUGAGAACAGAAAACAUGUUUCUUCUUCAUUUUGUUUAAAGAUUGCGUACCUAGGUAAGUCACACUGUAUAGAUAAAAACCUUCUUCUGUAUUCCUCACCUCUAAAUUAUAUGUUAUUUGCUAUUUGAAAACUGUAGUUAACUAUGGUUUUUUAUUAGUCUAUUAAAAGAUACGUGGAGAUAUUAAAUUAUACCUAAAGCAGACGUCCAACAAAUUCUGUACAUGCUGCUUUACAUCUUUGCAACAAACCUCUUAACUAGCAGCAUUAUUUCUAUAGUGUGAUUACCUGAGGGUGCCUCCAAAUGUAUAUCAUUUCACUCCCCUCCCCUCCCCACCCCCAAUAGAUUCAAAUAAAUAAAAUCCUGAGCAAAUUAAUAGCAAGUGUUAAUGUGAAUUGGUAGUAGGUUUAAGCUGUUGCUGAGUCGUCUAUAUGCCUGGUACUUCUCACAAUCUUUCAUACAUAGAAUUGUGCCUAGGAAAUAAUGAAUCAUAAAUAUUCUCUGAAGAAAAUGUGGUAAAGGUGUAACGGUGAAAUUUAUGUUCAGGCAGGGUACACAUGAGAUACUGCCCUUUAUGGAAAAGCAUAAGUCUCAGAAUCAAAAGAAAGCCUAAUAAAGAUUCUGGUCUAAGCCCUGAGAUCUUGCCUUCAGCCAGAGAAGGCAUUAUCAAUUACCCCCACCAGAUAUAGUAACUAAACCCAAAGUGAGUAAGAAACUUGGACAUAGUCAUGUAUUUAGUUAGUAACAAAAGCACCACUGGAAUUUAAGCUUCUCUGCUUUCUCAUGCAGUAUAUCUUGCUUCUCCCUGAGGAGACAGGGUUAUAAAUGAUCUUUUCCAGUGCAUUCGAUGUAACCAGCCAUUCUGUCAGAUGUUGCAUGGGCUGGAAACACUGCUUUUAAUUCAAGGCUAGUUCAUUCUCUGACUGUACCUGACAAACAAAACUCUCCCCGAGAAUUCAGGCAAAGGACACAAAGACUGGGUACUUGAGAGAAAGUGGGGAGAAUCCUUACAGAACACCAGAAGUCAGGAAGAAGGACAUUGAGCAAAAUAUAUCUGUAAGAGGGCAAGUCAGGCCAGUGUUAAGUCAACAAUCUAAAUCACCGUUUCUCAAAAUGUGAAAUUUAGAAAGACAGGGCUAGGAAUCUACAUCUUCAGCAAGAUUUCUGGAUGUCUGUUACACACACUGAAGUUUAAGAAUUUCCAAUCUACGUUAAUCGUAGUUUCCAAGAAAACACUAAUUGACAUUUCUAAAUAAAUUGAAGAGUCAUAAUAACAAGAAAGACGUAAAGAUUUGUUAUUAAUGGAAUCAUUAUGAGAAAAGAAAAGUGGACCCAUUUUAUCUCUAAGAAAACAAUUCAGUUGCAGCUUAUAUUUGUGCCUGCUACAUCCCAGGCACUGGUGUUUUAGAAUUUUUCCCAUGUAUCCUUUUUUUUUUUUUUUUUUUUUUUUAAUUCCCACAACAACCCAUUUCAAAAUGAGAAAACUAGGUUGAGUGACUUGUCCACAGUUCCAAAGCUAAUAAAAAUGAUGAGGCAUAUUUCUCUUCUGGGCCCACUGUAUUCAGUUCUUUGUUCUUUACACUGAGUGCCGAAAAAAAAAAUCAGACUAUUUUGAUUCUAGAAAGUGAGAUAAUUGAAAAUGUUAACAUAUUUCUCCAAAACUGAUCAGACUGUGGAGUCUGUCACUUUUUUGGUAUAAUAAAGGAGUUUGAAGAAACAAAUGACAUCAUUCCUGAUGAUGGUAGCCCACUCCAACAAAGGCGUAUAUAUGUAGGCAAGUUUGAAGAUAUCUAUAAGAGCAUUAAAAGGCAAGUGCACCAUUGUGGAAUAUCAUGACGAGUAGGCUUACAAACAGUAAAAAGAGACCAGAAACCACAAGUCUUACACUUUCAUUCUCUAAAUGCUUAUAUAAUUUCACUAAAAAAAGAAAAGCAGGUGCUGUGAUUUAGAACAACAGUUUUAUGUUAUUUUUAAAAAUUCAGAAUAACCAAUUGACUUUUUAAAUUAAAUAAACGUAGAGCAUAUAGUAAGUUUCCCCACAGGAAAGACAGAUGUUAACAAAAAUAAAAUAAAUGAUUAUUUGUGACCAUGUUACUAAUGAUGAAUCAGCAUCUUUGCCUCAAAUGAAAAUCUAUAAUUAUUUGUAUGAUAAAUUGGUAGACCUAGCCAAAAAUGUUCUCAUGAGACAUUCUGUGAUAUGUGUAAUUGAUUACUCCAAAAAUUAAGCUUUCUCUGAGGGUAACACAUUGUCAUCUCAUUGGUUUAAUGGGCUAUUUAAAUGUGCCUUAGCCACACAUUUGCUUAAUAGAAAGGAAUUAUUUUAAACUACCAAUCCAUAUGUUGAGUGGAAAGGAAGUUGGCCCACAUAUUCCAAUAAAUAUAUCAGCAAUAUAACAGUUUCAUCAUGGGACCAUGGAUACAGUGCAGGGAAAAAACAAACAAACAAUAUUUGAGAAAAUAUAUAUAUUCUGCCCAGCCACACUGGUGAGUUUUUAUUUCUUGUAUGAGUUUAAAUUGCCAACUUAAAAAAGCCUCAUUAGAAUUUGCUAUUCGAAAAGACCUUAAAAACCCUCACAGAGUUCUAAACAUCCCAUUCAUUGAAAAUAAUUUUCAGUUAAGUAGAUUUGUUUUGUGCACUUCACAACUUUUAGGUGACAUGAAUUUGAAGCGUAGCAAAAGAAAUGUAUAAAGAUAGCCUUUUCUGGUCAUUACCAUGUCUACUCAAGUUUCUGUUUUCUAGGUACACUCUAGCAUUGUAACUUUUUCCCCCUGAGAAGUAAUUUUAAGAUCUAUCAGUCUCAAUUUAAAUGAUCUGUUAAUCAGCCAGAGUUUUAGUUUCAUAAUAUCGUUCCAUUGCCUGACAAAGAUAUACACACUGAAGUGCCUUUAGCAGACCUGGGACCGUCAAGAAUCUUGUUACCCUGAUUAUUGCAAGAUGACAUAUUUCUUAAGCCAUUUAUAAUCUCAUAUUCGGGUUGAAUCUGAAUUUACAAAUAAAAGGGUUAAAUUGAGGCAGUUUCAAGCAGCAUUUAGGAAAAUGAAGUGGCUUCAAAUUUUAGUGUUUCUGGUUACAUUAUUUUGUUUGAAUUAUACAAUUACAUAAUUUUCUGUAACCAAAAUGGUAAUUUUGAUGGAUUUUUUAAAUGCCAAAAUCCAAUCAUCAAGGCCAAAGAAAUGCAUGAUUACUCUGAUUUCUUAUGCACCAUUCAGUCAAGACUUAACUCAGAGGCAGUUGAUUCAGUGCUUACAUCUAGACAAAGCUUUAAUGAGUGCAGACCCAGCCUAACAGUAUUUCAUCUAAUUUCUUUGAUGGCUUAAGCCAAUAAGCACUGAGGUAGCUUUUCUCAGAAGGAAACAGAUUUUAUUUUCCAGGGGCUAAUUAAUAUGCACCACCUAAGUCCCCAAAGGAUCACACAGGUGCCUGUAUCAUGCCAUAUGUCAUGUGCUAUAUUCCUGCAAGCUCAAGAGAUUAAUAUACAAUCAUUAUUAUGAAUUAUUAUGUUGCAUUGAAGUUAAUGUCGGUCUUUUGUUCUAAUUAAAGUACAAACGUGGCAUCUGAAUAGAAGCUUAGCUAGAGAAGUGGAGUUAGAGUCCCUAUUUUAAUGAACUACAUAUAUUUUUCAAUCAAAAUGUGUAAUUAUUUAAUUAUCUAGCCUGCUCAGUAAUCAUAACUCUCCAACUUCUUCAAAGGGCCUUUAUUCAAUAUGUUACCACUCAUAUGGUCAUUACUUGGUAAGUGUUUUAUAUUUUGAAUUUCUUAGAUGCUUUCAGUGUAUGUGCUAGUGUUUUAUUAAUAUUAAAAAUUUUUGUUUACUUAUAUAUCAAGCUGCUGCAAAUGGACUACCUUAUUUUAAAAGUUAGAAUAAAAUGCUAUUACUCUCUAAACAGAACUUUAGCAUAUCUGUUUGAUAAGAAAUACACAAACAAAAUAUUUUUCUAUGCUAUUGCAAAUUGUCCGCAGGAAGCAAAAUGCCAGAUGGUUAAGUGUAGCUCACAUAAUUAUAUUCCAAAGGUGUUAUAAACAAUUCUAUUUAGCAUCUGAGAUAGGUCUAUAUUAGGCAAUUUCAUGUUUACAUUUCUAACAGAAAGGUUUAAUGGCAAAUAUUCCUUAUAUUCUAACUUGCUACUUGGAGAAUAUGGAUAUUCUGAAAAGAAAAACCCUUUCUAGAACACUGUGCAGGACUAAUUUUUUUUUAAUAGACAUCCAGAAAAUAGCCUGGGCAACAAAGUGAGACCCUGUCUCUCUUAAAAAAAAAAAAAAAAAAAAAAAAAAAAGAAAAGAAAAAGUAGCUAGGCAUGUUGGUGUGCACCUUUGUAGUCCAGCUACUAGGGAGGCUGAGGCGGAAGAAUCAUUUGGGCCCAAAAGUUUGAAGCUGCAGUGAGCUAAAAUCAUGCCACUGUAGUCCAGCCUGUGUAACAGAACCUAUCUCAAAAAAAGGAAAAGAAAGUCACAUGCUGUUGAUAGUAGUUUUAUAUGUAUUUGGAAUGUUAAUAUGGGACACAUGCAUUUAAUACUUUAAUCAUGUAUUCAAUGUAGCAGCAUUUAGAUAUGUAAGAUUUUAGAAGUAAAAUCUCAGUGGUAUAACAUUUAAAACACAGCCUUAAAAUGAAGAAUAGGGAUGAGCAGGAGAAAAUUUAUAAAUUAACCCAGGGUAAAAUUUGGAGGAAAAUUUUUCCAAAUAAAUUUGCUUUGAUUAAAAACACAUAUCUCUCAAGAGGUGUCCCAAUUACUAAAUUAUGUUGAACUGUUGUGGUGUUUAGCCUUGUUCAAAAUGAUUUGAUUAUCAUCUGGAUUCAGAAAUCUUUUCAUUGUACAGAGAUUUCAUUGUCAUUGUCGUUGUUGUUAACUGAUUUUUAAUGAUAUUGAUUUAGAGGCAUUUGUCGGUAGUUUUUAAAUUACUAUAUAGGGUUGAAUGUCUAAUUUCUAUAAUGUGUGGAUGCCCAUCAGAUAUUUAGUGCAUUCUAUAUUUAGCCCAAGUGUGAUCACAAUUUAUUUUAUAACUUUUUAUGUGUUACUUACAUGACUCAAUAUGCAUCUUACUUAAGAAAUUAUGUUGUGAUCUGGAGUGACACAAAUGGAUUGAGAUACCACAUCCAUUAAAAAUAUAAGUGAAUAUUUUAUAUUUAAGUUGUUUAAAUAUUUGCACAUUAUUGAAAACAUAGUACUAGGAAAUGAAGGCACCAUUUAACAAACGUGUUCUGAAUCAUAAUUUUCAUGAGUUUGUACGUGAAAUGUUAAUGUUUAAAACACCCAUUUUGAAAUUAUUAAAUACAGGUAAAAACA